AAUUGGUACCAGGAGAGCCCAGAAGCCACACACGCAUCUCUGCCUCUUUGCUCUGGCUCUCCCACCCUCUUCCCGUCUUUCUCUGCUUCCUUGUCACUGUUACUCCAGGAGACGUUCACUUUUCACCAACCUUUCUCCAAGCAUCUCCAAGCCACUGACUAUAUAUAUUUUGCUACAAGAGACCUAGAAGAGGAAAAAAGGCACGAGACUUUUCAACACAUCGUUUAAAAAAAUCAUCAACGAAUUUCUUGCAAUGUUUGAGAACAAUUAAAAGGAAAAAGCGUUUUUUAAAAAAUCUAUCAACUAAGUGAACAAUCAUUCAUAUCGUCUACAUCCUGAGAUAUUAUUGUCCCUCGCUGCGGACACCAGCGAGAUGACAGCUGCUUUUUCAUUUUUGAAUGUAAUAAAUAUUUGCUGCUUUUAAUAUUUUCCGGAAUCUCCCCUCGCUAUUCCUUGGAAUUUUAACUCUAAAGAUUGGAGAACAGAUUAUCAAAAAGGCUUUUGCAAGCCUCCAAAAUGAUGCUGAGUCCGGACCAAGCAGCAGAUUCGGACCAUCCCAGCUCGGCGCACUCGGAUCCGGAGUCCCUGGGCGGCACGGACACCAAGGUGCUCGGCAGCGUGUCGGACCUGGAGCCGGUGGAGGAGGCCGAGGGCGACGGCAAGGGCGGCAGCCGAGCCGCGCUCUACCCGCACCCGCAGCAGCUGAGCCGCGAGGAGAAGCGCCGCCGCCGGCGCGCCACGGCCAAGUACCGCUCGGCCCACGCCACCCGCGAGCGCAUCCGCGUGGAAGCCUUCAACUUGGCCUUCGCCGAGCUCCGCAAAUUGCUGCCCACGCUGCCCCCGGACAAGAAGCUCUCCAAGAUCGAGAUCCUGCGCCUGGCCAUCUGCUACAUCUCCUAUCUCAACCACGUCCUGGACGUGUAGGGCGGGGUGCGCCGCGGGGGGCCGCCUGUCCCGGCGUCCGCGAAACGCUACGGAUCCGGACGGGCGCCGUCGCUCGGGUGGCGGAGGCUGCGGUGGCCCAGCGAGACGGCCGCCUCGAGAGACGGCCGGGGAAGAAGCUCGCUACCUGUUCUCUCUGGUCAGCAGGGCGACGAGGGAAGGUUUCCGACGCAGGCAGGAGAGGAUCUUUGCAAUGUCAUUUCAAAUCCAAAGCUGCUGAGCACCCUCCAAGAGAGACAAGCAUGGUGGCAGUCUGCUAGACCAGAGGGUGACUGGCUCAUUCCCUGAGCACAGCGCAGACACAGUGAUUAUUCGCCCAUCCAUGAGGUCUCGAUUCUUCUUUGAAUGACGAUGCCACUCAACAACUUGCCAGGCCAUUGCUGCUCCCCAGAAAGCCUAGCCCCAGCUGGCCCAGCGGACAAGACUGCCUGUGCUGAAUAUUUCUCCACCCAAAUGGACUUCCCCUCACUUCUACCACUGCCCGGAAACUUCCAGAGAACAAGGGUAAAAGUAUUGGGCAAAACAACCUUCCUCUCCAGGGAGAGGGGAAGAGGAGGGGCAGUGUAUGAUGGGAUGGGAUGGUAAAGGAAGGGCCGACUGAGGAGAGAGGAAUGGGUAAGGAGGAAAUGAGACUGGGUGGGAGUGGGGGACUCUGGAGGGAAUACCCGCUUCCCACAGGAAUGCUGUUUGCAGGAGCUCCCUCCAGUGGCCCUGCCCCAUGAACACGUAUCACCAGAGCACUAUGAUAAGGCGAGUAGCCAGAGCCAGCCUCUGUGAUGCUGUGAUUUAUCCAACUCUCCUCACUGCUGUCUCUGGCUACCAGUUUUCUUGCUGAUGUUUGGGGUGGAGAGAAUUUAAGGGGAGAAGAGGGCCAACUUAAGAGCAUGCACAGCCAAUACCCUUUUCCAUAUUUAGAUGUGCUAUCUCAUUUAUCAGUAUUAGUAGUCGAAAUAAUAGCUAAUGUGGGUUGAGUGUAUACUACAUGCUUACUAAAGUGCUUUGCAUGCAUUAUCUCCUGUAAUUCUCACAACCACCCAGUGAGGUAGGUACUUUUAUUGUCUCCAUUUAACAGAUGAGGAAUUUGAGGCUUAAAGAAAUUAGAUGACUUGCUUAGGGCCAUGAAGCCAUGUUUAUCAGUUUAUCAAAGUGCCUGCCCCUACCCAUCAUCCUCUAGAGUUGUCCUUUGAUAGAGGGGUAGCUGUGCCACUCACACACCACCCCCCUUGGUGCCUGCACUGCAUCUUUCCAUCCAUGUGCCUAGGGAAAGCUUCAGCUCAUGUAAUGCCUAAGGAGUGCUGCGUCUGCAGUACACACAGCUGCCCAACCAAUGGGACCAGUGGAGGCCAAAACCAAGCCUGUGCUCUGUAUGCCAAGUCAAGCAUGUGCCUUGGCUUGAAGUUGGACUACCUGGAGGAAGGGGAGCAUUUUUCUACUUUGCAAGAAAACACUAUAGGAUAAUGGUGGCCCUGUGACAACUCCCCCACCAGGGCACCGUCAUUCACUACCACAUGGGUGAGGCUGGCUCCAUCCACACUCCUCUGCACCUUCCAGCCCAUUCUCACGCUGCUUCUAGACCUAUCUUUAAAAAUUAGCGUGCCAUCCUCCUUCGUGAAUGUCCAUUUUAUUUUUUAAUAAAAUUCAAGUUCCCAAUCUAGGCAUAGAAAUGUUUCACAGUCUUGUUCCAGACCCUCACUAGUGCCAUUUUCAGCCACUCUCCAGAGAUUAAAUAUUCCUGCAAACUCGGUUUCCUCACUUCCCCAGAGAGGCCAAGUCUUUUUCUUUUACGACCUGGGCCUUUGUAUUUACUUCCCCUUUACUCACAAUGCUCUCCCCUAACCUCAUUUUUUACCCAGAAAAUUCCGAUGAUUCCACUGUGACCCAACUCAGACCACACGUAACCACACGUAUCAUUACAAAGCUUUCCGUUUCUUUCAGAAGCAUUAGCUGCUCUGUUCUCUGAGUCCCACAUACAUACAUCGUUUUAACUGAAUUUACCUGUUUCUCCCAUCUCUGUGUUUGAGACCCAAGACUCUGGAGCCAAGUUCGGGCCCUGGCUCCAAUUAUUCUAAGUGUAUGACAUUGAACAUGUUACUAUAUCUCCUCAAGCCUCCAUUUUCAUCCAUAAGAUGGGACAACGUAUGUACCAAUCUCAAAUGCAUGUCAUGAGGUUUCCAUGGGAUAAUGUAUAGUGCUUAUCAGAAUAGGAAUACAUGGGAAGUGCUCAAUAAAUGUGAGCUAUUUUCAUUACCUUUGUAUUUAUAAUAUGCACAGGAAUUAACAUAGGAUAAGCUAAAAUCAGCUUUAAUUCUUUAAUAUAGUAAUGAUUUGUGGUUUCCACCAACUAUAUCCAUCUGCAUAUGAUACAUUACUAACUCAACAGUCAGCCAGAAAUCAUCCCCAUCUUCUAAGACAGGAAGCAUAGGUAAAUUAAUAGUCAUCCAUGGAAUACACCACACAUGCACACCUGUAGAGUUAUCUACAGGUCUGAAAGCCCCACUCGACUCAUGAUAAAGGCCCAGUCUAUGCCUUUUCUCUUUUACCUUGGUUUUUCCCAUAGCACGAAUGCUGUGAUAAGCACUAUAGCAGACUGGUCAGAAGCACAGACUCUGUCAAAGCUAAUUUUUAAAGAUAGGUCUAGAAGCAGAGGGCCAGUUUUCAGGCCUGCUCACCCAUGAUAGGUCAGGCAGAGGGGGAUGAGCGGGCACUCACAUCCAAUGUGUGUGUACGAGCAAUUGCCAAAGUUAAGGACGACAAGGGGUAAAUUUUUUUUUUUUUUUUUGAGACCAAGUCUCGCUCUGUGGCCCAGGCUGCAGUGGUGCAGUGGCGCAAUCUUGGCUCACUGCAACCUCCACCUCCCAGGUUCAGGCAAUUCUUCUGGCUCAGCCUCCCGAGUAGCUGGGAUUACAGGCAUGUACCACCAUGCCCAGCUAAUUUUUUGUAUUUUUUGUAGAGACGGGGUUUCACCAUGUUGGCCAGGCUGGUCUUGAACUCCUGACCUCAGGUGAUCCGCCCCCCCCUAGGCCUUUCAAAGUGCUGGGAUUACAGGCGUGAGCCACCGCGCCCAGCCAGACAAGGGGUACAUUUUUAAGAUAGAAGGAAAAGUCAUCAGGGAAGGUGGGUUAGAUCAGCUGUGAAAGUCCCCUCAAAUAUGCAAGUGCUCACAGAUGAUUUUCAGGAAAUACUGUUCGUUUUACUGUGAUAAUGGUAUAUUUGUUGUUAAAAGAAAAAAGAGUCCUUAUCUUUUAAGAGAUACUUACUGAUGUCUUCAUGGAUGAAAUGAUGUGAUGUUUGGGAUUUGCUUCAAAAAGUCUUAAGGGGUAGUGAGAAAGACAGGAUAAGAAAAUAAAUGAAAUGUACUUA